GCCAUGGGUUGGAGAGGGCAGCUCGGGUAGAGAGGGCUGGCGGAGCGGCGCAGACGGCGGCAGUCCUGCUCAGCCUCUGCCCGGCUCCGUACUCCGGCCCCGGCCUGCGCCCUCAGAAAGGUGGGGCCCGAACCAUGAGCUCCUACCUGGAGUACGUGUCAUGCAGCAGCAGCGGCGGGGUCGGCGGCGACGUGCUCAGCUUGGCACCCAAGUUCUGCCGCUCCGACGCCCGGCCCGUGGCUCUGCAGCCCGCCUUCCCUCUGGGCAACGGCGACGGCGCCUUCGUCAGCUGUCUGCCCCUGGCCGCCGCCCGACCCUCGCCUUCGCCCCCGGCCGCCCCCGCGCGGCCGUCCGUACCGCCUCCGGCCGCGCCCCAGUACGCGCAGUGCACCCUGGAGGGGGCCUACGAACCUGGUGCCGCACCUGCCGCGGCAGCUGGGGGCGCGGACUACGGCUUCCUGGGGUCCGGGCCGGCGUACGACUUCCCGGGCGUGCUGGGGCGGGCGGCCGACGACGGCGGGUCUCACGUCCACUACGCCACCUCGGCCGUCUUCUCGGGCGGCGGCUCUUUCCUCCUCAGCGGCCAGGUGGAUUACGCGGCCUUCGGCGAACCCGGCCCUUUUCCGGCUUGUCUCAAAGCGUCAGCCGACGGCCACCCUGGUGCUUUCCAGACCGCAUCCCCGGCCCCAGGCACCUACCCCAAGUCCGUCUCUCCCGCCUCCGGCCUCCCUGCCGCCUUCAGCACGUUCGAGUGGAUGAAAGUGAAGAGGAAUGCCUCUAAGAAAGACAGCGGUUUGGGUUUUGUGGAGGAGACGCGUUCCCGGGCGAAUUCCAUGGAGUCUGCCUCGAGUACAGAUUCGGAAAAUGUGCCAGGCAUUGAGAAAAUUUCAGGAAGGAGCUCUCCGUGGAACUUCUCCUGGCAAACUCGCCGAGUAUGGGGCCGCUAGCCCCUCCAGCGCGAUCCGCACGAAUUUCAGCACCAAGCAACUGACAGAACUGGAAAAAGAGUUUCAUUUCAAUAAGUACUUAACUCGAGCCCGGCGCAUCGAGAUAGCCAACUGCUUGCACCUGAAUGACACGCAAGUCAAAAUCUGGUUCCAGAACCGCAGGAUGAAACAGAAGAAAAGGGAACGAGAAGGGCUUCUGGCCACGGCCAUUCCUGUGGCUCCCCUCCAACUUCCCCUCUCUGGAACAACCCCCACUAAGUUUAUCAAGAACCCCGGCAGCCCUUCUCAGUCCCAAGAGCCUUCGUGAGGCCGGUACUUGGGGCCGAAAAACUGUGGCCUGCAGAAGUCCCAGGCGACCCCCAUCCCUAUCUAGACUUAGGAGCUCAGUUUGGGAUGGAGGUGGGAGAACAAAAAUGAAUAGGGAUUUCACUUGGGAAAUGAAGUACUUUAGUUGGCUUCCGAGUUCCAGACUAUAUGUCCAGAUAUUAAUUGACUGUCUUGUAAGCCACUUGUUUGGUUAUGAUUUGUGUCUUAUCAGGGAAAAGGUGCCCAGCUGCCAGCCCAGCUCCGCUGCUAUCUUUGCCUCACUUAGUCAUGUGCAAUUCGCGUUGCAGAGUGGCAGACCAUUAGUUGCUGAGUUCUGUCAGCACUCUGAUGUGCUCAGAAGAGCACCUGCCCAAAGUUUUUCUGGUUUUAAUUUAAAGGACAAGGCUACAUAUAUUCAGCUUUUUGAGAUGACCAAAGCUAGUUAGGGUCUCCUUGAUGUAGCUAAGCUGCUUCAGUGAUCUUCACAUUUGCACUCCAGUUUUUUUUUCUUUAAAAAAGCGGUUUCUACCUCUCUAUGUGCCUGAGUGAUGAUACAAUCGCUGUUUAGUUACUAGAUGAACAAAUCCACAGAAUGGGUAAAGAGUAGAAUCUGAACUAUAUCUUGACAAAUAUUAUUCAAACUUGAAUGUAAAUAUAUACAGUAUGUAUAUUUUUUAAAAAGAUUUGCUUGCAAUGACCUUAUAAGUGACAUUUAAUGUCAUAGCAUGUAAAGGGUUUUUUUUGUAAUAAAAAUUAUAGAAUCUGC